GCAGUAGCUGAGCAGUGGCAGCAGAGAGGCAGACGUGAGCUGAGGGCGCAGAGGCAGGCAGGUGAGAGCGGGAGCUGGAGCAGCAGCUGGGGAGGCAGCGGGAGGGGCCUUCCCGGUCCCCAGGCUGCGGGGCAGGCCAGAGGCCCUGGGACACACGGGCAGGCAUCUCUGAGGGUCCCCAAGGAACAUGGCUGGGAGCCGUGAGGUGGUGGCCAUGGACUGCGAGAUGGUGGGGCUGGGGCCCCACCGGGAGAGUGGCCUGGCUCGUUGCAGCCUCGUGAACGUCCACGGUGCUGUGCUGUACGACAAGUUCAUCCGGCCUGAGGGAGAGAUCACCGAUUACAGAACCCGGGUCAGCGGGGUCACCCCUCAGCACAUGGUGGGGGCCACACCAUUUGCCGUGGCCAGGCUAGAGGUCCCCUUCCCAUCCUCUCCAACGGCAGCUGAGUGAAAGCAAGCUGACUGGCCUGUGUGACCAGAGCAGGGCAGGCUGUCCAUGUGGGAGGCGAGGCGAGGAACGCGGGGCUGGGGCAGUCACAGCUGGGCGCCUGGGCUGCUGGAGGCCUGGAGUGGUCGUUCACUCUUCUGGCUCAGUGUGGCAGUGGCAGGCGGGCUCUGGAUUCAUCCCACUGGCUUCAAGGCCUGGCUUUGCCACUAACUAGCCGUGUGACUGUCCCAGUUAUCAAAUGGUGCUUGGCAAAUCACACCAAAACUUACCGGUUCAAACAAUGUCAAUACUUAUUUCGCUCGGCCACCUGCAGUUUGGGCAGGUGCUCUGCAGCAGGACAGGCCGUCAGUUAAGGCACCUUGAAGGCUGGGGGCUGGAACCAUUGGAAGGUUUGCUCACCCACCUGUCUGGUGGCUGGUGCUGGCCUGCCUUGGACACAUCACUAUCUCGGUGGCUUUUCCCCGUGGUCUUUCCAGCAUGGUGGCUUUGGGGUGGCCAGACAUUUAUUUAUUUAUUUAUUUAUUGAGACGGAGUCGUGCUCAGUCGCCCAAGCUGUAGUGCAGUGGCACGAUCUCAGCUCACUUGCAAUCUCCCUCCCAGGCUCAAGCAAUUCUCCUGCCUCAGCCUCCCGAGUAACUGGGAAUAGCCACGGCGCAUGGGUAAUUUUUGCAUUUUUAGUAGAGACAGAGUCUCACCAUGUUGGCCAGGCUGGUCUCAAACUCCUGGCCUCAGGUGAUCCACCUGCCUCACCUCCCAAAGUGCUGGGAUUACAGACGUGAGACACCGUGCCUGGCUGGUGGCCGGACUUCUUAUAGAAUUGCGGUCCCAGAGAGAAGUCAGAAGUCAUACAGGCCAGCCCAUAUGCAAUGGGAGGGGAGUUUGAUUCCAUCUUUUUUAAGAAGAGUGUCAAGGAAUUUGCAAACUUGUUUUAAAAUCAUCAGAGUAAGCCUGGGCAUGUCACUCCUCUGCAUUUCAGAUAUUUCCUUUGUAAAACUCAGUUAAAUGCAGUGCUCCCUCCUCACUGUUAGUUUUCUGUGGCUGCCGUAAGGAAGCCAUCAACUUAGUGAUUCACAGCAACACAGAUGUCUUCUCUUACAGUUCUGUAGUUUCGAAGUUCAGCGUGGGUCUCACUGGUCUAAAAUCAAAGUGUCAGUGGGGCUAGGUUCCUUCUGGAUGCUCUGGGGAAGAAUCCAUUUCCUCGCCCUUUCUGGCUUCUAGAGGCUGCCUGAAUACCUUAACUCACGGCCCCUCCCUCCAUCUUCAAAGCCAGCAACAGCCUGUUUUCCUCAUGUGGAUUCACUCUGACCUCCACAUGUAAGGAGGCUUGUGAUUAUGUUGGGACCACAUGGGUAGGCCAGGUGAUCUCCCCAUUUGAAGGUCGACUGAUUAGCAAUCUAAGUUCUGCCCGGAACUUUAAUUCCUCUUUGCCAGGUAAUGCAUUCACAGAUCCUGGGGACUAGGGUGUGGACAUCUUUGGGAGGUCAUUAUUCUGCCUGCCAUAAUAGAAUUGUUGGGAAGAUUAAACAACAUAAUAUACAUGACGUAUGUUGAGGCACGCUUGGCACCUGGGAAAUACUCAGGAUGUACUAACCAUUGCUCCUACACAGUUCAGCUCCUGAAGGAGUCCAGGUGGGCUUUUGGCACAGAAUGAAACUAUCAGGUGUGAGGAGGGUCCUAGUGCAAUCUCUUCUUUUCAAAGAUGAUACAUUUGAAGCCCAGGGAGGACUGAUAAUUUGCCCAAGGUCACACAGCCAGUCAAGGAGGGAUUGCUCCCUUGCCAGCCCCAGCCCCACCCAGAAGAUGCUGGGUCAUGUAGGGGUGGGCACAUGUCUUCCUGGCCAGAUCCUGCAGCUCCUGAAAGGCAAGCUGGUGGUGGGUCAUGACCUGAAGCACGACUUCCAGGCACUGAAAGAGGACAUGAGCGGCUACACAAUCUACGACACGUCCACUGACAGGCUGUUGUGGCGUGAGGCCAAGCUGGACCACUGCAGGCGUGUCUCCCUGCGGGUGCUGAGUGAGCGCCUCCUACACAAGAGCAUCCAGAACAGCCUGCUUGGACACAGCUCGGUGGAAGAUGCGAGGGCAACGAUGGAGCUCUAUCAAAUCUCCCAGAGAAUCCGAGCCCGCCGAGGGCUGCCCCGCCUGGCUGUGUCAGACUGAAGCCCCAUCCAGCCCGUUCCGCAGGGACUAGAGGCUUUCGGCUUUUUGGGACAGCAACUACCUUGCUUUUGGAAAAUACAUUUUUAAUAGUAAAGUGGCUCUAUAUUUUCUCUACGCCAUCACUGGGUCCUCUUCUUAUUCUUCUCUCCAAGCUGGGUUAACAGUAGACAGGACCCAUUUCUGUGUGAUGUUAGGAGGGAAUGAAGUCUUAUGCUGGGGAGGUGGGCAAGUAUCAAUUUCCUUAAUAUCUUGAAUCCUGUGGGUCCAAAAUGUGGCUUGGAAAUCUAAGUAGCAUGUGGCUUAAUUACUAAUCCCACCCUUUGCUGUUGCAUCCCAGCCCUAUUCCUGGUGCAUUUAUGCCCAGAGAGGUGGCAUUAUUUCCUGGGGUGGCAUUCAGCUCCUCUUGAGUUGGUGCCACAGCAUUUGUGGGCUUUGAAGCAAAGGUACAGGAAAUGUCAAGGGUGCCACCCCGGCAACCUUGAGCAAGUCACCCCUCCUAUUUGUAAAAUGAGGAAGGAAAGGUAACAAACUGUGGAGUCAGAGAGAAGUAGGUUGGAAUCCUCUUUGUCAUUUAGUAGCUGUUUGACCUAAGGUGGUUUACUGAACUUCUCAGUUUCUCCAUCUGUAAAAUGAGAAUUCUAGCAACUCGUAGGGUAUUUGUGAGAUGUUGCAGGCAAAGCCCCCAGCACCAUGCCUGUCCUAGCUUAAGCACCCACCAGGUGUCGAUAAGUAAUUGUUCUUCCCUGGACUGCCUGCACAUCUAGGGCACCCCAGGAAGAGUCACCGCACUCUGUUUCGGGGCUCGGCUCUCUGAGGGGAGGGCAUCCUGUAUGGGGAGGAGGGUCUGGACCAGAGCUGUCCCUGAUCGCUAGAAUCAACGGCAGAAUUCUUGUUAUUUUAAUAAUAAUUAAUAAUUUAGUGCUUCCACUAAAUAAAAAUCAUUGGAAUGGUG